AGUGCACACCUGCUGGUACGAGCAAAAGUAGCCGACAGGCCAGAGUUUCCAGUUUCGGUGGCUUCGUAGGCUUUUAGCUUCUGAAAUCCGCUAAAAGCGGCGGUUCAUUCAUCUUCAAGUACCUAGCCUGACUGGUAGGGCUGCUCAGCAUUCCGAAACAUUUCGACCUGGGGAGGGGGGCGGCGGUGAAAGAAUACUUUCUGUAGAGAGUGCCCCUCGCGUCGCCCCUGCUUUGAAGGCUUUAUGUAUUAACGGAAUGCCGAACAUUUGUGUCCUACUUGCUGACAGCGCACAGGAUCCUUCUAACAGUAUUUCUCAAGUACUUAACAAAAAGAUGAAAACUUGAAGUCCAAGCCGUGCUGCUGAUUCCGUCUCACAGUUUAAAGACUGUCCAGAAACUUUAAGCUUUCAAAACUGUACAUUUUAAAAUCCUGUGCGUUUAUCUUCAUUUUGCUGGGCAGAAAGCCAAAGUACUGGACUGCCUGGUUCAGGGCUGAACGCCUAGUACACCUGCUAACUUGGAGCUUCAGAGCCAUGGCAACCAAGGAGUCAAGAGACGCCAAAGCACAGUUGGCCCUCUCCUCAUCGGCCAAUCAGAGCAAGGAAGUGCCUGAAAACCCAAACUAUGCUCUCAAAUGUACUCUUGUGGGACACACGGAAGCAGUGUCAUCAGUUAAGUUUAGUCCUAAUGGAGAAUGGCUAGCAAGUUCUUCUGCUGAUAGGCUAAUCAUAAUUUGGGGAGCAUAUGAUGGAAAAUAUGAGAAAACACUCUAUGGUCAUAAUUUGGAAAUAUCGGAUGUUGCCUGGUCAUCAGAUUCCAGUCGUCUUGUUUCUGCCUCAGAUGAUAAAACUCUAAAAUUAUGGGAUGUGAGAUCUGGAAAAUGUUUGAAAACACUGAAGGGGCACAGUAAUUAUGUCUUUUGUUGUAACUUCAAUCCGCCAUCCAACCUUAUAAUCUCGGGAUCUUUUGAUGAGACUGUAAAAAUAUGGGAGGUGAAAACAGGAAAGUGUCUCAAGACUUUGUCUGCUCAUUCUGACCCAGUUUCUGCUGUUCAUUUUAAUUGUAGUGGGUCCUUGAUAGUGUCAGGUAGCUAUGAUGGCCUCUGUAGAAUCUGGGAUGCUGCAUCAGGUCAGUGUUUAAAAACGCUCGUUGAUGACGAUAACCCUCCUGUCUCUUUUGUAAAAUUUUCUCCAAAUGGUAAAUACAUUCUCACUGCAACUUUGGACAACACUCUUAAACUAUGGGAUUAUAGCAGAGGCAGGUGCCUGAAAACAUACACUGGUCAUAAGAAUGAGAAAUAUUGCAUAUUUGCCAAUUUUUCAGUUACUGGUGGAAAGUGGAUUGUGUCUGGUUCCGAGGAUAACCUGGUUUACAUUUGGAACCUUCAGACUAAAGAGAUUGUGCAGAAAUUACAAGGCCAUACAGAUGUUGUGAUCUCAGCAGCUUGUCAUCCUACAGAAAACCUCAUCGCAUCAGCAGCAUUAGAAAAUGACAAAACAAUUAAACUGUGGAUGAGUAACCACUAAUCCCUUUGAAAAUCAAGUAGUAGAGCCAAGUUGGCCAAAAAACUUGGAUAUUUAAAAAGACGGUUUCUUUUAAUUUUGGCAGUUUGGUAUUUUAAAAAUUGUCUAUUGUUAAAUUUUGAGAUUCAUACACUACAUUUACAAAAUGAGAUAGUUGAAAAAGCACAUCUAGAAUUCAGCUUCUGACUACCAAUCUUUUUUGAGCAACUUUUUGUAAUUUUUAUGGAUUUAUGUCACUUUUAUUACAGGGAUAUAUUGCAUAGUGGUGAAAUCUGGGCUUAGUAUACCCUCACCCAAAUAGUAUACAUUGUACCUAGUAAAUACUUUCCCAUCUCUCACCCCACUCCCACCUUUGAAGGCUCUAGUGUCUAUGAUUCUGCUCUCCACGUCCAGGUGUACACAUUGUUUAUCUCCCACUUACGAGAACAUGUGGUUUUUGACUUUCUGUAUCAUUACUUCACUUAAUGGCCUCCAGGUCCAUCCAUGUUGUUGCAAAAGAUAAGAUUUCAUUAUUUUUUUUUGGCUGAGUAGUAUUCUGUGGUGUGUAUGUGUGUGUGUGUAUGCAUAUAUGUGUAUGUGUAUGUAUAUAAGUAUAUACACCACAUUAUCCAGUCAUCUGGAUAUGUAUAUAAGUAUAUACACCACAUUUUCUUUAUCCAGUCAUCUCUUGAUGGACCCUUAGGUUGGUUCCAUAACUUUGCUAUUACGAAUAGUGCUGCGAUAAACAGCACUAUUAUGAAUAGUGCUGCGAUAAACAGUGCAGGUGAUUUUAAAAUAUAAUUUCCUUUGGGUAGAUACCUACUAGUGGGAUUGCUGGAUCGAAUGGUAGUUUUUAGUUGGAAAAUCUCCAUACUGUUUUCCAGAGGUUGUAAAAUGUACAUUCCUCCCCACAGUGUAUAAGCUGUGCCUUUACUCUGCAUCUUUGCCAUGAUUCUUUUUGAGACAGAGUCUCUGGUGCCCAGGCUGGAGUGCAGUGGCACAAUCUUGGCUCACUGCAACCUCUGCCUCCCGGGUUCAAGCAGUUCUCAUGUCUCAACAUCCCAGGUAGCUAGGAUUACAGGCGUGCCACCAUGCCUGGCUAAUGUUUCUAUUUUUAGUAGAGACAGGGUUUCACCAUGUUCGAGGCUGGUCUUGAACUCCUGGCCUCAAGUGAUCCACCUGCCUCGGCCUCCCAAAGUGCUGGGAUUACAGGCAUGAGCCACUGUACCCAGCCAUUUUUUGACUUUUUAAUAAUAGCCAUUCUAACUGGUUUAAGAGAGUAUCUCAUUGUGGUUAUAUUUUGUAUUCCUCUGAUGAUUAGUGAUGUUGAGCAUUUUUUUGUGUGUGUUUGUUGGCCACUUGUAUGUCUUCUUUGAAAACUGACUUCUAAUCUUGAGGCCUAUUAAUAAUUUCAUUUGUCUGUCACUGGACAAUUUCUCAUUCCUCUCAGUGACUAUCCUAGAGGAUCAGUGUAUUUGAGAAAUAUUUAGAAGUAAAGUUGACAGGACAGGAUGAUUGAUUAAAAGAGGGGAGCAAGGGAAUUUGAAAUAAUUCCAGGGUUUCUGGUUUGGGAGAUCAGAUGAACAAGUGCAUAAGCCUGGGAUGCUGGUGGAGGACUGGAGAGACAUGGCAGAUGCUACCUGCACACUUUUGGUAAUAUUCUGUGUGAUGGGAUAUGAAAUGGUCCAUAGAAAAAAACCGGAAAAAUACGCCAAGGUUAGGUUCAUUCUAAGAGUCUAAAAAUUUCAAAAACCAAAACAACAUUAUAAAUGGUGUUUCUCAAGGACCUUUCACUACCUUUUUAGAUUGUGCUUGUGAUUUUCAGGCAAGCUAAAUGUCUGAUGAAGACUGCUCUUCUUUUGUUCUGUGUCUGACCUACUAAUUCCUGCCCAUGCUUCAAACUCAGUUCAGAAAUCACUGAAGGAACCAUCCACUGCCGGCCUGCCUGCAACCACAGCUGACAGCUGAGUUAGUUAGGUUUUCCUGUCCCUAUUAUUUACCAGUUUGUACUGAAAUGCUUUCAUGGGCUGUGCUUCCAGAUUAUGAGUUCUGUGGAAUCAGGAAGUAUGUCUCUGUAUUCUUGUAUUCUUUGGCUUUUUUGUGUAGUAAAGGGACUCAAGUAAUGUUUGACAGUGAAGGAUACAACUUCAUUCCUUGCCUGCUUUGAUAAAUUUUAGUAAUAAAUUCCCAAAACUAUCAUGUUGAUUAAAAAUAAAAAGUAACCGUAACCUCACACAUUAACUUUAUUCAAACAAACAGCACUUACAGGAAAUGUAAAGUAGAAAAAGAUUUCUGCCCACUUUACCUACGGAGACAUGAUAAACACGCAAAAAAAACCUAGAAAUUAAGCAAAAAAUAGCACAAUAAUUUAACUGAAAGCAACAAGGGCAAAACUGUCUCCUUUUGUAGUUUGUGGUACCUUAUAGUAGUGCUCAUUCAGUUUCGUUUGCUUGAUAAAUCUGAGGACUAUGAGAUAUCAGAGUUACUAGUAGGGUAGGAGUGCUGUAAGGGUACUGGGAGAAGUAGGAUUAGUUAGGGGCAGAUCUUGAAUUCUGGCCAAGAAACUGAUAUUUAACCCAUAAAGAGAUAGUCACUAUAUGUUAUCAAAUAGGAGAAUAACACAAAUGAGAAAUGACUGUUAAUUCCUGAUGCAUAAUAACAGUUGUGAGCUUUAGUUUAAUGUAAUAUUUGUAAUAAAAACGUUUGGCCAGGCA